AGUGCAGUGUGGGUUGGGGCCGGGGGUGGGGGGCAGAGGGGGGUGGCCCAGGUGGCCCUAGGACCCCCCCUCCAUGGAAAACCAGCUAUGGCAUAACACCGUGAGAUGUUGCAAUCAAUACCAAGAAAGCCCCCACGAUGCCGAGGACAUCUUACUCCUGCUGCUGGGCCUCAUCGUUCUUGUCAACAUUGGCAUCAACGUGGCAACUAUGAUGUGGCAUGGACUCCAGAACGCCUUAGACAAGAUGAUUGAUUGGGCUACUCAGAAAAAUGAAAUUCAGGCCAGUGAAAGUCCCCCAAGUGGUCCCCCAGACAAGGCUCAGGAUGUCCACAUCCACUGCAUCCUGGACCCUGUGCAGGUGAAGAUGUCCCGACCCACGCAGUACUCCUCUUUCUCCUGCCACCAUUUCUCCAACCAUCACAGUAGCAGUCUUCUUCGCUGUGUUCGUCGCCGCCGCCGCCGCCACCGCCGUUGUCGCCGUCGCUGCUGCAACCACCAGCAGCGGCCGCAGAACUACAGACAAAUCCCCCAUAGCCACUCAGUCUUCCGUAACCCACAUCGCAGCCAAAAGAUGUCACAACUACACCGAGUGCCUUUCUUUGAUCAGGAGGACCCGGAUUCCUACCUGGAGGAGGAGGACAACCUGCCCUUCCCGUAUCCCAAGUACCCACGUCGCGGCUGGGGCGGGUUUUAUCAGAGAGCGGGCCUGCCCUCCAAUGUGGGGCUGUGGGGCCACCAGGGUGGUAUCCUGGCCAGUCUGCCACCACCCUCUCUCUACCUGUCACCUGAGCUGCGCUGCAUGCCCAAGCGUGUAGAGGCCAGGUCUGAGCUGAGGCUGCAGUCCUAUGGGCGCCACGGUUCCCAAUCCCGACUGUGGGGCAAUGUGGAGGCUGAGCAGUGGGCCUCGUCUCCACCACCUCCCCACCGGCUGCCCCCUAACCCCUCUUGGGUCCCCGUGGGGCACAGCCCUUACCCCUCAGUGGGCUGGAUGCUGUAUGACUCCUGGGAUCAGCGGCGUCGUGGCACGGAGGGCUUUGAGCGCCCCCCUGCCUCGGUGUCCCGGAACGCCCGGCCUGAGGCCCAGGGCUGCCGGGAGCACCACUCCCCACAGUCCCACCAGCAGAGCCUGCUUGGUCACGCCUAUGGCCAGUCCCACCGCAGUCCCCACCCAUCCACGGAACCCUUGGGCUACAGCUCCCAGGACCCCCGUGAGGUGCGGCGUCGGGCAGCUGACUGGGCUGAGGCUCUGCCCGCCUGGCGUCCUCUGACUACCUCUGCCUCCCUCACGGUGUUGGACGAGGCCUCCCAUCAACGGACCCCAGCUCCAAGCUCAGUGCUGGUCCCCCAUUCCUCCCAGCCCUGGCCCAAAGUCCAGGCUGCGGACCCUGCCCCUCCCCCGACCAUGUUUGUCCCACUCAGCCGGAAUCCAGGGGGCAAUGCCAACUACCAGGUGUACGACAGCCUGGAGCUGAAGCGGCAGGUGCAGAAGAGCAGAGCCAGGUCCAGCUCACUGCCACCGGCUUCCACCUCCACCUUGAGGCCCUCUCUGCACAGGAGCCAGACCGAGAAACUCAACUGACCAGCAGGCGGAUGUGGGGUGUGGGGCAGGGCAUGGAGGGAGAGGAAUAAAGAGAAACAGAGUCCAGGAAA